CCAGAAAUCCAAUGACUUGUCAGCCAGAGUAACGGCUGUUGUCAGGUCUUCAGGGUCUCGAGGGUCUUACUCUGUCACCUAGGCUGGAGUACAGUAGUGCGAUCAUGGUUCACUGUAGCCUCGACCUCCCGGGCUCAAGCAAUCCUCCCACCUCAGCUGGCUAAGUAGCUGGAACUACAGACAUGUGCCACCAUGCCUCAUUAAGGGAGAAGAAAGGCAUGAGGAAAAGAGGAAGAUUGUUAUUGUCAAUAUAUUUCAUAUUGGAAAAGGGCUCCAUGCCACAUUUUUGUUCUGUGGCCUUAGCGCCUCUCUCAGCCUAGUUUUCUUUAGCUGUAGAACAGGGAUCCUAGUACUGCAUAAAGUGUUUGUGAAGAAGAAUACAUUAGCUAAUAACAUAAAGGUUUUAAUACAGUGCAUAUCAUACAGCCUGGCCAACAUGGCGAAACCCCAUCUCUACUAAAAAUACAAAAAAUCAGCUGGGCGUGAUGGUGUGCCUAUAGUUGCUGCUACUUGGGAGGCUGAGGCAGGAGAAUCAAUUGAGCCUGUGAGGCGGGGGUUGCAGUGAGCUGAGAUCGCGCCACAGCACUCCAGCCUGGGCGACAGAGUGAGUGAGACUCCAUCCCAAAAAAAUAAAUAAAUAAAGCCUAUCUUCCGGCCAGAAUAUAAACUCCAUGGAUGGCAUUUGUCUCAGUUAACACUCUUUCUCUAAUAGCUCCUGAAUUGCCUGCUAGAAUCGCCUAUAGGAAGACAUGACAUUAUGGGGAAUGCGUUAAGUAGCUCCCAACAUGGUCAUGUGCUCACACUAGGACUAAGAUACUGUUAUUAAAUAAAUCAUGGAAAAAUGAACUUAGAAAGGGAUAUGAAGGAUUAGCCAGUAAGUCUCUAUAAAACAUAAGGGAAUUAUAUCCAUAUUACCUUGUAUAUAAAAUGCCUUAUUUUUCAGCAUUCUUUUUUUUGUUGUUUUUUUGAGACAGGAUCUCUUACUCUAUGGCCCAGGCUGGAUUGCAGUGGCAUGAUCUUGGCUCGCUGCAGUCUCAACCUCCUGGGCUCAAGCAGUCCUCCCACUACAGCCUCCCGAGUAGCUGGGACUACGGGUGUGCAUCACCAUGCCAGGCUAAUUUUUGUAUUUUUCGUAGAGGGGGUUUCCACCAUGUCACCCAGGCUGGUCUCGAACUCCUGAGCUCAAGCAAUCUGCCUGCCUUGGCCUCUCAAAUUGCUGAGAUUUCACACGCAUGAGCCCAGCCAUUUUUCAGCACAUUCUUUAGGCAAUUUCCUUUCAGCAUUUUAGAGUAGUAAGUACUCUAAGUAGAAUUUACCAAGUUCUUGGUCUUCAUAAAUUGACAACCUCUUAUUUUGUAGGUUAUAGUGCCAUCAUGUGGAUACUUUGUUUUCUUCAAAUAAAAUGUAACCUUUUUAUAACAGAGACUAGAAAACCCAGCCAUCCCAACACCCAGGAUAGAGGCACUCUCCAUUCCUGAUUGUUCCAAGGCUCAAGUGGUCAGAAAUGACUGGGAAGAAGGGAGAAAAACUCAGGUGGCAAAGGACAUGGACGAAAACCCAUGGCGACAUGGAAAGAAAACCCUGUGAUAUAGAGAGGAAAAGCACAGGACAGCUUAUUGGGGAGAAUGGAACUCUUCUGUAUCCUGAUUGCGGUGAUGGCCACGCAUGGCUAUUUCAACACUACACUUGCACAAUGUCUUUGAAACCAAGAGUAGUAGAUUUUGAUGAAACAUGGAACAAACUUUUGACGACAAUAAAAGCCGUGGUCAUGUUGGAAUACGUCGAAAGAGCAACAUGGAAUGACCGUUUCUCAGAUAUCUAUGCUUUAUGUGUGGCCUAUCCUGAACCCCUUGGAGAAAGACUUUAUACAGAAACUAAGAUUUUUUUGGAAAAUCAUGUUCGGCAUUUGCAUAAGAGAGUUUUGGAGUCAGAAGAACAAGUACUUGUUAUGUAUCAUAGGUACUGGGAAGAAUACAGCAAGGGUGCAGACUAUAUGGACUGCUUAUAUAGGUAUCUCAACACCCAGUUUAUUAAAAAGAAUAAAUUAACAGAAGCGGACCUUCAGUAUGGCUAUGGUGGUGUAGAUAUGAAUGAACCACUUAUGGAAAUAGGAGAGCUAGCAUUGGAUAUGUGGAGGAAAUUGAUGGUUGAACCACUUCAGGCCAUCCUUAUCCGAAUGCUGCUCCGAGAAAUCAAAAAUGAUCGUGGUGGAGAAGACCCAAACCAGAAAGUAAUCCAUGGGGUUAUUAACUCCUUUGUUCAUGUUGAACAGUAUAAGAAAAAAUUCCCCUUAAAGUUUUAUCAGGAAAUUUUUGAGUCUCCCUUUCUGACUGAAACAGGAGAGUAUUACAAACAAGAAGCUUCAAAUUUAUUACAAGAAUCAAACUGCUCACAGUAUAUGGAAAAGGUUCUAGGUAGAUUAAAAGAUGAAGAAAUUCGAUGUCGAAAAUACCUACAUCCAAGUUCAUAUACUAAGGUGAUUCAUGAAUGUCAACAACGAAUGGUAGCAGACCACUUACAGUUUUUACAUGCAGAAUGUCAUAAUAUAAUUCGACAAGAGAAAAAAAAUGACAUGGCAAAUAUGUACGUCUUACUCCGUGCUGUGUCCACUGGUUUACCUCAUAUGAUUCAGGAGCUGCAAAACCACAUCCAUGAUGAGGGCCUUCGAGCAACCAGCAACCUUACUCAGGAAAACAUGCCAACACUAUUUGUGGAGUCAGUUUUGGAAGUGCAUGGUAAAUUUGUUCAGCUUAUCAACACUGUUUUGAAUGGUGAUCAGCAUUUUAUGAGUGCGUUGGAUAAGGCCCUUACGUCAGUUGUAAAUUACAGAGAACCUAAGUCUGUUUGCAAAGCACCUGAACUGCUUGCUAAGUACUGUGACAACUUACUGAAGAAGUCAGCGAAAGGGAUGACAGAGAAUGAAGUGGAAGACAGGCUCACGAGCUUCAUCACAGUGUUCAAAUACAUUGAUGACAAGGACGUCUUUCAAAAGUUCUACGCAAGAAUGCUGGCAAAACGUUUAAUUCAUGGGUUAUCCAUGUCUAUGGACUCUGAAGAAGCCAUGAUCAACAAAUUAAAGCAAGCCUGUGGUUAUGAGUUUACCAGCAAGCUACAUCGGAUGUAUACAGAUAUGAGUGUCAGCGCUGAUCUCAACAAUAAGUUCAACAAUUUUAUCAAAAACCAAGACACAGUAAUAGAUUUGGGAAUUAGUUUUCAAAUAUAUGUUCUACAGGCUGGUGCGUGGCCUCUUACUCAGGCUCCUUCAUCUACGUUUGCAAUUCCCCAGGAAUUAGAAAAAAGUGUACAGAUGUUUGAAUUAUUUUAUAGCCAACAUUUCAGUGGAAGGAAACUUACAUGGUUACAUUAUCUGUGUACAGGUGAAGUUAAAAUGAACUAUUUGGGCAAACCAUAUGUAGCCAUGGUUACAACAUACCAAAUGGCAGUUCUUCUUGCCUUUAACAACAGUGAAACUGUCAGUUAUAAAGAGCUUCAGGACAGCACUCAGAUGAAUGAAAAGGAACUGACAAAAACAAUCAAAUCAUUACUUGAUGUGAAAAUGAUUAACCAUGAUUCAGAAAAGGAAGAUAUUGAUGCAGAAUCUUCGUUUUCAUUAAAUAUGAACUUUAGCAGUAAAAGAACAAAAUUUAAAAUUACUACAUCAAUGCAGAAAGACACACCACAAGAAAUGGAGCAGACUAGAAGUGCAGUUGAUGAGGACCGGAAAAUGUAUCUCCAAGCUGCUAUAGUUCGUAUCAUGAAAGCACGAAAAGUGCUUCGGCACAAUGCCCUUAUUCAAGAGGUGAUUAGCCAGUCAAGAGCUAGGUUUAAUCCCAGUAUCAGCAUGAUUAAGAAGUGUAUUGAAGUUCUGAUAGACAAACAAUACAUAGAACGCAGCCAGGCGUCGGCAGAUGAAUACAGCUACGUCGCGUGAUGUCGCUCUCCUCCAGCGUGGUGUGAGAAGAUCAUUGCCAUCACCAUUUGGUGUGUUCCUGUGGGAAAAAGCAGGACUGUGCCUCCAUAAUUUGGUCAUUUGGCAGCCCCUGUUUUCUGCUGUUUACAACAUCACCAGUGCCACGUCAUGAGCGUCAAAGAAAAUGCCUAGAGAUAUUUCAAGCUCAUGUCAUUAUGACAUUUCUUAAAACUUUAUUAAAAGAAUGAGUGAAGUAUUGCUGAAAAGUGGAAAUUCGGUUGGGUACCAUGCUUUUUCUCCCCUUCACGUUUGCAGUUGAUGUGUCUUUUUUUUUUUUUUUAAUGUAUCUUAAAGGACAUAAAAUUUAAAAACUUAAAUAUUGUAAUAUGACAGAUAACCUAAUAAUUGUAUCUACAUUAAAAUGACAAACAUGAUACUGCUGCUUGUCAAAUAAAAAAAAAAUAAAGAAAUAGAAUGCCUUUUUUAUGUGGAUGGAGUAUCAGGUUGACCACAAAAUAUAUUGACUCAAAGCAGCUAAUGCAUCUUUAGUUGCGUUUUUAUCUGAAUGGUUUAAUUCACUUGUACUCCUAUUUAAAUCCUACAUGAAAAAUGUCUAGAUUAUUGUUCUUGACUGCAUAGGACUGCAUUCAGCAUAAAGAAUGCUUUAUUUUUAUGGAUUAGAUAUAUUGGAUCUAAACAUUUUGAAUCUUGAAGAUGUAAUUCCAUCAGCAGUUUCUGGUGGUGUGCUACUCCACAGACAUCGCAGAGUGUGAGCAGGAUGCUUGGUGACCUCAAGUCUGGCACAGAGAGAGCUUUUCAUUCAAAAGUUGUCUUUCUUCGGUUGCAUAAUCCAUUAAUUCUAGCAUAGACUAGUACCCUAGCUCUGUGGCCUUCCCUGAGUCUUAGGAAAUCUAUGAUACCAACAUAUUCCUUCUAUAUGCCUCCCCUACCUGUUACCCUUACAACCCUCCUCCAACAGUUUAGAUACUAGAGUCACUCUCAUCAAUCACAGAUGUGCUUAGCAAUGCAUAACCUAAAUACUUUUUUAAAAAAGAAAAUUGUACAUUGUACUGGGUGCCACAUAUAUAAAUCCCAUUAUUUUGUUUAUUUUAUAUAUAUAUAUAUAUAUAAUAUAUAUAUAUAUAUAUCUCAACAGCAGUGUUAAGAGUACUGCGAUCUAUUAUCAUAUUUAUUGUCUAUCCACACCAUCACCACCACCACCACACCCCUCCUCCCUCAACAUACAAUUUUUCUUUAUUUUAAAAAAAAUAAGAGACGGGGUUUCGCCAUGUUUCCCAGGCUAGUCUGGAACUUCUGGCCUCAAGCAAUCCUAUCUCUGUCUCCCAAAGUGCUGGGAUUACAAGCAUGAGCCACUGCAUCCAUCCAACACAAAAUUUUUAAAAUCGGAAUAUUUUAAAGCAAAUCACACAAAUUAUUUCACUUAUAAUACUUCAGUAAGGCCUUUAAAAAAUCCACAGUGAUAUUAUUACUCCUAACAAAAACAAUAAUUACUUAGUAUCAUCUAAUAUGUGGUUCAUAUUUAAAUUUGUUGUUUUGAGAUGGGUCUUACAAUUGGUUUAUUCAAUUGCAUUUUUUCUAACUCGUGUCUCAAGUGUUUUAAAAAUCUACUGAACUUAUAAUGACUUAUAUAAUGUAUUUCUCAUUUUACCUUUCUUCCAAAAGAGGAAAUAAUGGCAAACCAUAUAAUAUUGUACAUUCACUGUCAAAAAGCAAACCCUUGUUUUGAUAACUUGUUGAUUGAUAAAAGUUUUCCAAAUUGA